CUCUAGUGGCAGCCGGUUUUGAGGCCGGCCUCCGGCUUUGAAGUUCCUCACCGCGUCUCCUUCCCUCUCCCCAAAGCCUGGAUCACCGCCCAGCGUCAGGCGAGGGGCGACGUCUCGAGGUAAAACGGAGGAGGUGCGGGACGCGGAGACUGCGCGGGCCCGGUAGCCCUGGAGAGGCCGAGGCUCUAGGCCGCGAGGGGCGGGUGCAAUGGCGGAGGAACAGGUGAACCGCAGCGCCGGCCUGGCCCCCGACUGUGAGGCCUCGGCGACUGCAGAAACUACGGUUUCCUCAGUGGGGACCUGUGAAGCCGCUGGCAAGUCACCAGAGCCCAAGGACUACGACAGCACCUGCGUGUUCUGCCGGAUCGCGGGGCGGCAGGACCCGGGCACCGAACUCCUGCACUGCGAGAAUGAGGACCUAAUUUGCUUCAAAGAUAUCAAACCAGCAGCAACUCAUCAUUAUCUUGUGGUGCCAAAGAAGCAUAUUGGAAACUGCAGAACUCUAAGGAAAGAUCAAGUAGAACUGGUUGAGAACAUGGUAACUGUUGGAAAAACCAUUCUUGAAAGAAAUAAUUUCACUGACUUCACGAAUGUGAGGAUGGGUUUUCAUAUGCCACCAUUCUGUUCCAUUUCCCACUUGCACCUUCAUGUUCUGGCACCAGUGGAUCAGCUUGGCUUCUUAUCCAAGUUGGUUUAUAGAGUCAAUUCCUAUUGGUUUAUCACAGCUGAUCACUUGAUUGAAAAACUAAGAACAUGAAAAUGUCAAGAGUGGAAGAUUUUUCUAAUCUUGGUUCAGCAUGAAGUGGUAUUUAGGUCCCUUUUAAGUCUAAUUGCAAUUUUAAGAUUUGUUGGGUUUUAUGAGAGGCUGUUACUUAGUGGCCUUAAAUCUUUUCUGAAUGUCUGUUUCCUAAGAUCUGUGAUACAGUUAUGUGAAUAUUUUGUUACUGACUUGUUUCAAUGGUUACUUGUAUAAGGAUUUUAUAUAUAUGAUACUAUAGAUAAAAUCCUAUUUAAGACAAAUUCUGUUAAUCAACAAGGGCUCUGUAUUUUUUUAAGUUAAAAUAUUUUCAUUUCUCAGUAAGUAGUCAGUUAUAAUAGUGAUUUAUUUAUGAAGAAUAAACUACUAUAGAAAGUACUUUGUGGGAACCUUUAUUACUGUGAAGGAGAAAAAUAGCUAUUUCUUGACAGUUCUAUAGUUAUACACAUAAAUUUUCAAAAUAAAGAAUACCAUACUACACAAUGAUCUCUGAUUUUGCUGAGGGAAGGAAUUAUAUAUGUGCCACUUUUUCCUCAAAUUUCAGAUGCCAGUUUUCACUUUUUGAAGCAUUGCAUCUUUUUAAUAAAUCUAUCCUGAAAGCUAUAUAAUAUAUAUAAUUUAUAUCAAUGAAUUUACAAUAACUAUCAAAUUGGCUAUCAGAAUUCACUGUAAUGGAAUUUUGCCUCUAAUAACAUAAAGGGGGAAGAAACAUAAAGUGGUUCUCUUAAUAAAACUAGCAGAAAAUGUUGCUUUAUGGCAUGUUUUUGUAUCAAAGAGAAAUCAGAGGUUAAACUUUGCUUUUAUCAUGAAAAGGGCCUGAUUUGAAGGUAGAGAUAGGCUUAGAUGAGAAAAAUUGAUAACGCAAUGUUAAUACUAUUGAUAUUUCAUAGGUAUAUUUUGUUAGAAAUUGGUUUUUUGGUGCUAAUCUAUAGGCACAAUAGUGAAUAUGAAUGAAGAGUAGGUGCUGCAAGUUAAUCCUACAUUGUGCCAGUGUAUAUUAGUACCAUGUAAAUGAAUAUGAAUAAAUGAACAUGAGGAUUAACGAACUGUUGAAAAUAGGCUGAGAUACUAGUUUUCUUUCUUUUUUAGAGGGGGCAUGAUAUUAAAGAUAGUUUUAAGUAACAAAUUACUUAUUACAAAGUUACAACAUGUGGAAUCAAUAGUUUUAUUUGUUCAUUAAUUUAUUCAUUCAGCAAACAUUUGUUGAACAUUUAAUGUGUACCAGAUAUUGCCAGGAUCAGGAAAUAAAGAACUAAAAAUGGACAUUCAGACUGCAAUUGCUAGUACAGGGGUCAAACAAAAUCAGUGAUUAGAAUUUAGUGCGUUAAGUUCCCUGAUGCCUUCACAGCCAGAAGAGGCUGUGAAGGGAUAAACACUUCUGAGAGUGGGUGGUAGUAGAACUGAGUAUUCAAGACUGAAUGUUAGGCAGGUAGACAGUGACUGGUUAGGCUGAGAAACUUACAAGUAUUUUCGUUGAGUUCUGCUUCCACUAUUAUUUACUUUACAAUGGAUAUGAAGUUCAGAUUUCAUCUUAUUUACUGAAGGUGGAGAAAGGAUGUGGAAGUAGGGGUUAUGGGCUCUCAAAAGUAGAUUUAGAGAGAUUUUUUUAUCACUGUUUUAUGAUAUAGUUCACUGAGCACUUACAUAGAUUAACAGUUACAAGUUUCCAUAAAUCAGUUAGAAUAUGACUAGCUUCAGGGAAGGAAUUUUCAACAACUGCAAUCUUUGAUUGUUUUACUGUGGGAACUUGCAGUGAUAUAAUUGACAACAUUAUUUAACAAUAAUAGGUAAAGUAGGCCGGGUGUGGUGGCUCACGCCUGUAAUCCUAGCACUUUGGGAGGCCGAGGUGGGUGGAUCACAAGGUCAGGAGUUCGAGACCAGCCUGGCCAAUAUGGUGAAACCCCGUCUCUUCUAAAAAAAUACAAAAAUUAGCCGGGUAUGGUGGCGCAUGCCUGUAGUCCCAGCUACUGGGGAGGCUGAGGCAAGAGAAUUGCUUGAACUCGGGAGGCGGAGGUCGCAGUGAGCCGAGAUCGUGCCACUGCACUCCAGCCUGGGUGACAGAGUGAGACUUUGUCUCAAAGAAAAAAAAACAAUAAUAGGUAAAGUAUUUAAGGAAUUCUCAGAUGCCUUAUGGACCUCUUCAAAAAUGUGGUUAGCCAAUUGAUUCAACUUUUAUAGGUUUAUAUGCUCUCAUGUAAACCUAUUUGUUUCCGAGAUCAGACGAGAUCGGGCGCGUUCAGGGUGGUAUGGCCGUAGACAACCUAUUUGUUAAAAACCCUUGGAAACACAUCUUUUAGUAGAGGUUCUUAUUUACUUAUAAAGAUUAAUAAUCAAAUUACUACAAUUAAUAUCCAUUUAGCCUUUUCAGUAGUCUAAAUAUUUGGUAACUCCCUAGCCAUCUAUAACACUAGUUCAAAACAAGGCUAAUUCAUAACCUGUCUUAAAAAUGUUUGAAGUGGUAUCAAGAGCAUUGUUUAUGCAUGUUGUGAUACUAUUUGUGGAACUGUUUAAUGAGCUAUUUCAAACUGCUAGAAGAAAAUGAAAUAAAAAUGGAAAAAUACUGUCAAA